GGGCGGAGCGGCCAACAUGGCGGAACGCAGGAGACACAAGAAGCGGAUCCAGGUAGCAAAGCCGAGCUCUGGGCAGGGGGCUUCGGCGCGCUGGAUAGUGGAAGGGGCGGGGAAAGCCCCCUAAAAGGGCGAGCGAAAGCAAGGGCGAGGUGGGGUGGGGUGGGGUGGGGUUCCGCCGCGAGGCAGCUGGCUGCAGGCUGCGCGUUGUGAGGGGCCUGAGGGGGGGCGGUGUUGGCGACGGCGGAGACAGAGACGGAGGUGGUGGUGGAGCAGCAGGGGAAGGAAGGAGGCGCCGCGCUCAGAAUCCGGCUGCGGAGGCGCGGCUGUGGGCCUGGAGUUCCUGUGGUCGCGCUGUCCCGGGCCUGAGCUGGAAGGUCAGCCUCCCCUGGGGCGCAGACGCUGACCCUUCCCGGGGCUCCUCCCCUCCCUUCACCCCAUCCUCUGGCCUUAGCUGGCCUGAAAUUAAGGCCACGGUAAUAGGGGUAGCAGGAGGCGGCGGACUGACCUAAAGCAGCUGGUUCUUUGUGCGCAUAGACCGUAAGGGGGAAUGAUCUGGACUUGGUCAGCUGCCUCGGGGCCUAGGCAGGGAUCUGCUCAUCCAGAUGUUCAGUUGCGUUGCCCUUCUUUCCCUUCAAUAUUAUUAACUUAAUAGUCCACUUGAAGCUUGCCGGCUUUUUUCCGGGCGACGUGGUGUAAACAACCACAACCUCGUUGGUGCUGCAACGAGCUGGUGGAGCCCAGAAACCUUUCACAUGCCAGUGUGUCAUCCUCGUAGUAACGUACAUAACAUCUCCCCCUAAUUCCACAUGCGUGUCAUUUGUGCAUUUCUUCCUUGCGAUUUUCCCUGGUUCUUGUUCUUUGCCAAGAGGAUUAAUUAUGUAGAACAUCUUGGACUCAGGAUAUUUAUUAGUCGUCUCAUCAGCUGAUGUGCUGAGAAACCUUCAUAAGCCCUCAAAUUGAUCACAUGUAGUAAAUUGUUACUAUAAUCAUAAAUUGUUACAUUCAUCAUUGCCUUUCUGUUCCUUACUAUUUCAUUGCUUAGAAUGAUUUUUUCUUUCUUCCAUUUUAUCCCUUCUUUUUUUUUUUAAGUUUAUCGAUUUAUUGGCGUACAAUACAGAUGUUUUGAGCUAUGCAAGUUAAAAUUCUUCUGUAAACUUUUUAAGUGCUGUGAAAAAGACACACAUGAUCAGUAAAUUUGGAAUUUUGGAAUUUGGCAGAAAUAAAGUAGUUCCGAACAGGGUGCAGAAGGGAAUUAGAAAGAGGCAGAUUUCGAGUUCAGACAGAUAAGACUAGGUCUUAAGAUCAGUAGAAGUUUCUAAUUAUACUGUUCUUAAUCUUUCAAGAGUUAGUGUUAUUCCUCUGACGUGGGUAUACAGUAUUUUAUUAGAUUGUAUAUUGAAAUUGUCUGUCAGAUUUGUACUUACAGAACUCCUUAGAUUUACACUUGACAGUACAAUUUUAUGCCCUUCAAUACACAUUGUUUUACAAUUCCAGUUGCUCUUUAAUAUUGUUGUAAGGGCUAUAUAAUUCACCUUUUGAAUAGCUGCUCUUAUUUAGUUGUGAUCUUAUAUUAAACAGAGGCUGUGGAGUAAUGUGACAGUGGCAGAGAGCUAAAACUUGAGCCAAACUGCCUGUUUGUACCCCACCUCCACCAAUUAUUGGCUGAGUAACUUUGAGCAAGUUAAUUUUUACCUCCCUGUCUGCAUCGGUAAGAAAACAUAUUUACCUCAAAAAAAAAAAAAGCAAGAAAAAAGAAAAACUUUAAGAUUGCUGUGAAAAUAAUAGUAUAAUUUCAGAUUCUCGUGUCCCAUCGAAGUUUCUAGCAAGAGGACUGUUGUCACAUUUCCUUCUUGGACUCAUUACUGGUCACUGAAAACCAGAAGAAGUUGGUGAACCAUCUAAAGAAGAGAAGGCUGUGGCCAAGUAUCUUCGAUUCAACUGUCCAACAAAGUCCACCAAUAUGAUGGGUCACCGGGUUGAUUAUUUUAUUGCUUCAAAAGCAGUGGACUGUCUUUUGGAUUCAAAGUGGGCAAAGGCCAAGAAAGGAGAGGAAGCUUUAUUUACAACCAGGGAGUCUGUGGUUGACUACUGCAACAGGCUUUUAAAGAAGCAGUUUUUUCACCGAGCCCUAAAAGUAAUGAAAAUGAAAUAUGAUAAAGACAUAAAGAAAGAAAAAGAUAAAGGAAAAGCUGAAAGUGGAAAAGAAGAAGAUAAAAAGAGCAAGAAAGAAAAUAUAAAGGAUGAGAAGACAAAAAAAGAAAAAGAGAAAAAAAAAGAUGGUGAAAAGGAAGAAUCCAAAAAGGAGGAAACUCCAGGAACUCCUAAAAAGAAGGAAACUAAGAAAAAAUUCAAACUUGAGCCACAUGAUGAUCAGGUUUUUCUGGAUGGAAAUGAGGUGUAUGUAUGGAUCUAUGACCCAGUUCACUUUAAAACAUUUGUCAUGGGAUUAAUUCUUGUGAUUGCAGUAAUAGCGGCCACCCUCUUCCCCCUUUGGCCAGCAGAAAUGAGAGUAGGUGUUUAUUACCUCAGUGUGGGUGCAGGCUGUUUUGUAGCCAGUAUUCUUCUCCUUGCUGUUGCUCGAUGCAUUCUAUUUCUCAUCAUUUGGCUCAUAACUGGAGGAAGGCACCACUUUUGGUUCUUGCCAAAUCUGACUGCUGAUGUGGGCUUCAUUGACUCCUUCAGGCCUCUGUACACACAUGAAUACAAAGGACCAAAAGCAGACUUAAAGAAAGAUGAGAAGUCUGAAACCAAAAAGCAACAGAAGUCCGACAGUGAGGAAAAGUCAGACAGUGAGAAAAAGGAAGAUGAGGAGGGGAAAGUAGGACCAGGAAAUCAUGGAACAGAAGGCUCGGGGGGAGAACGGCAUUCAGACACGGACAGUGACAGGAGGGAAGAUGAUCGAUCCCAGCACAGUAGUGGAAAUGGAAAUGAUUUUGAAAUGAUAACAAAAGAGGAACUGGAACAGCAAACAGAUGGGGAUUGUGAAGAGGAUGAGGAAGAGGAAAAUGAUGGAGAAACACCUAAAUCUUCACAUGAAAAAUCAUAAUCUGACUAAUUUUGGGACUGAAUGAAUAAGUACAAGAGGUUGGAUUUUCUAUGUUGGCUGAUUACCAUAUUGAACACAUGGCAUUUGUAGCAUUCUUUAAAUCUAUCUACUGAAAUGUAUUUGACAUUCAAGCAGUUAUAUUCGGUCCUUCAUUUUAUAGAAUAUUGGCACUAUUAUUGGUACAGUUUAAAGCCAUUAAUAUGUUUUAUCCAUUUGAUAAUUUUACAGUAAGUAGGUCUCAUUCAUUUUGACAGUUAUCAAAGAUGUACUUUCCACAGUUAAAUUUACAUUAAUGGCAAUUUUUGAUAGUUUUAUGGCUUUUUACUGUUAGACUAAUCAAAAAUAACUUUAAAAGGAACAAAGAAACUCCAACAUUUCACAUUAUGCAUAGUUAUGUAGCCAUUUCACAGUUUCUUUAAGAUGUGUAAACUCAUUGUCCUUGAUAGUUUUUAUUUUUCAUUAUAAAAUUAUACCAGGAGAUUUCUUUUAAGAUUCUGAGUUAGCAGAGUUCAAAACUAUUUUGUGGAAACAAGCCAACUAGUAACAAUGCAGCAACACUUCUGGUUUAGCUAAAUUAUUUUUCCAAUGUAGGAAAUCCACACUGAUUUGUACGUCUGACUGAGAGAAAGAUGGUCGUCUCCAGCAGAGAAAGUGAACAGCAUUUGUUGGAAGGUGAUGGCUCUCCCUCCUCCCUCCCCAUUUCAUUGGCGUAACGUAAAGUGUAUUCUGUACAUAAUUUACAAAUAAAACAUUUUAUUUUAAUUGUUACUUAUUAUUUAGAUAUUUCUCAACACUUAAAUUCAUAAAAUUAAGACCAUGUAAGGGUAUGUUUUUAGAGAAAUGGAAGUUUGAGUAACCCACAGAACAUCUGUGAUCUUUCUACAGCAGCUUCAGUUUUGUGCCAACAUUCCAUGUAUUUUGAAUAUGAGCAAAAACUGAUCUUAAGAGCAGACUUAAAGUAGCUUUGUACGCCUUAAUGUUCAUUUUGAUUUAUUUUAAAUCUUUACAUUCAGAAAUGAGAUACUGUAUUAUCAGACCAGGAGGCAUUGCUGUGAAAGAUAAUUUCCUAUUCUAAAAUAUCAAAUUUAAAAUAAAGAUAAUGAAAGAAAACAUAAGAGAACUAUUGGACUCUAAUUGCUUUGAACUAGUUUUGCAGUUUGACUUUACGUCUUAUACAUCUUAGUUACAAGUCUUUGGAAACUCUUGUUUACUUAUGAGCAUAAUCAUUCCUUGGAGUUAUACUAACUAAUAAUGAAUAUUAAAUGAUUUUUCUUCAGUCACAGUGAGAGCAUCUUGCUUUGUGGUUGAAAUAGGUAGUGUAUGUCAGUCUUUGCUUUAGGCUGUUUCUCAUCUAAGUGUUUGAAUUAAAGAUGUUAAAUUUUUCUAAUUGUGAAAAAUAUGUUUUCUGUAUCGACACAUUUUAUUAAACUUGGCUUGAUUGCUUCUUUAUAGUAGUCCCUGUAAGUGGACAUAAAUGUGGCUAUUUGAUGUUAAUGCAACUAUGUCAAGGCUGCAAUCACUUUAAUAGUUUCUUUUUAGCAAAUAAAUGUUCAUUGAUGAAGUGCCUGGGUAUUUUCCCGUCCCAUUUGCAGAGCUCUACUACUUCAUUUCCACAGUAAGCAUAUAUAUAAUGAUCACUUCUGAGUUUAUCACCAGUAACAUUGAUACCUAUUUUGGGGUAUAAACAUGGUGUUUUUCAGAAAUAAAAAUUAUUUCAUUAACCUUUACUAUUACUGUGAUAAUACCCAGGCACUCAAUAUUCAUCCUGAAAUUUUUUAUAAUAUAUGUAAUUUGUCUAGUCUUAAAGACAUUUGGAGCAUGGCCAACAGGAAGGUCAGCUUCUUACUGAUGUGUGUGGAUUCUUACAGAAUGUUAGUACAAAUUUUUAUAAAUAUUUGGUGAUCCCUGGGGGGAAAUAUCAUUCUUACUAUGGUUAGAAAGUGAAUUAGAAAUUUCAGCUCAGUUUCUAUUUUACUAUUCAAGUUGUGUACUUUAAACAAAUAUAAAAAUCAAAAGGCUGCCUCUAUUACAAUCCUCAGUGGAAUAGAUGGCUAUCUUUCUUGGCUAACAUUAAAUAUUCUUGUACCAGAGCAUGGAAAAUCGUUUAUAAUUGUUAAUAGAAUGGCGAUUUUUUUUUAAGAACUUCAGAUUUGCUAUGCUGCUGUAAGUAGAAAGCAUGAAGCUUUUUGAUCAUGUAGGGCUUAUUGUAGAGGGUAUCAAUUGGCCUAACUAAGCAGGAUUGAAUUUACCAGAGGCUAAGUUCAGAUAGUAAGAAUAAUGCAUAUGUGAUUGUUCUUAAAGUCAAUGUAUUAAAUAAGGUAUUUUUCCUUUUCCCUCUUACUGGAUUUUUCAAUUUUCAAACCAUAUGGCCUAGGUAACUUUAAUUGAAAUAAUAUAGAUUUAGUUGAAUACUAUUCAGGAAGUAAUAAAUUUUAAUAUAUCACAUUGAAAUUAUGCAGUGGUGAUGAAUUUUGGUGUUUCCCCCCUCUUUCUGGUUUUACAUCAUGAGGAUCAGUUAGCUGCUGACAAGAAAAGUCAUCUUGUGUCUUUUGUAAAUUGAAUUUUUUUUUUAAAUCUAUUAGGAACUGGAAAACAGCAAGUAUGGUUGAUUCUCAUUAUUCAAGGUAGUUACGUUCUAUAAAGUCACUGCGAACACUGAAUUAGCAAAUAUAGAACCUAGGGGAAAUACAAGGCUAGAUUUCUGCAAGCCACUGGUCACAUUUUCAUCAAGCAGUCAACAUGUAAAUUUCUGUUGUAAAGACACCUUAUUUAAUAUAAUCGAUUCAUUAACAUUGAAGUCAUGACCAACAACACUGUAACUCAUGCCUGAAUGAAGCUUAUCUGACACAUAAGCUUCAUAAGGCACACAACAGCCUUUUUACCCUUAGGAACAGCUUUUUGCCCUUAGCACUAUGCUUGGGGGCCAUUUUAAACAGUGAAAUCAAAAAAAGAACAGAAAUGCAAAAACCAUGGCAUUAGCGUAAAAAGGACACGUUUAUAGUAUGAAAGCUGGAACAUGGCCUUGUUCAACCUCAGCUCAGAAUAUGUGUACAGCAAGUUUUUUGCUGUACCACAAAAUUUUAGGUUAGGCAAAUUCACAAAUACGGAAUCCAUGAAUAACGAGGAUCAACUGUACUUAACUAUAUUUUAAAGCUGUGACAUUUAUCUACCUGGUUUAUGGAAUAGAAUUUAUUGCUGAAUCAUGCUCCAGUAUUUGAGUGAUGUUUUAAAUAUCCUAUGUCUGAAAAUAAUUCCUCCUAAUUGUGUGGUAAUUUGCUUUUACUGUUUCCACAGUAUUUCAGGUCUUUGCUCAUUCACUCAGUAAUACUGAGCACUUACCAUGUACCAGAAUUUUACUAGGCACAACCAUGAAUAAAAAUACAAUUCUCUUGCACCAUUAAAUAGUGUGUUAAGUGCUACGGCAGCAAAUUGCUACAUGUGCUGGAUAUCUCUUGUUUUCCCCUCCAGCUCCACUCUGCUCUUGCCCACAAAGCUGACCCGAAUGGACCACAGCAGUGGGCUCCUAUGCCUCCUGGCUUCUGAGUGGGUUUGGCCAAGGAGUGUCCUGGCCAGAGAUCAGAGGAUGGUAGGGUGCCUAUUCUCGGCUCUUCUCCUGGGGUUGGGGGGCUGCCUUAGCAGCCAAAGGUCACUUCUCCCAAACUCCUUCCCUGCUUUCCAGGUUGCCAGUCCCUGCACUCUUCCUUUCUGGCCAAGGAUGAUGUCAGUUCUGCUGCUACUAGCCUGGAGUUGCAGAAGCUACUGUGCUUCCUCUUUGGGUAGCCUAUACCUAUACUUAUCUCCUCAUAAUAUCUUCAUGUAAAGAACCAUCUGUUUCUUAUUGGAAUCAAGACCAAUACCAAGGAGAAAUUCCUAGGGAACAAAAAUUCCAAUGAGGAAUUGACCUCUUUGUCAGAUCCUUAUCACCAAACAUUAGAAAAGAUCUCAUAACUUUAUACAGCAUGUUGUAAGCAUUUUGAUAACUAAAAUCCUGUUCUAGUGAAUGUCAUGCAGAUAACUACACAAGGAGAUUAAUUUAAAUUUGCCUUCUUUGGCAAGCCCUUAAACCAAUGGCUAAAGCAGUUAGUUGUGAGUUUCUGAGUAGGUCCCAAUGCGUUUAUUUCAUUUGUCCAACCUAGCACAGAGAUCCUUUGAUACUUUAAUUGCAUGGCUUUUCCAAUCAGACGAAAUUUCAGUCUGAGAGAGGACAUAUUUUCUGAGGUUUAUAGUUUUAGGAUUGUCCAAAAGGCCUAUGAUCUCUUCUUAGCAUGACAGAAAGAGGGAAAGAUAAGUUAAAUUUCAAGGGGGUCAUAUCAUCACACUUUGGUCUUAUUUCAUUUUCAAUGAUUUCCUAGAUCACUUUAACUUUUUUGUGUCAUGGACUCCUCAGAAUAAUGGGUUUUUUUUGUUUGUUUGUUUGUUUGAGAUGGAGUCUCACUCUGUCACCCAGGCUGGAGUGCAGUGGCGAAAUCUCAGCUCACUGCAACCUCCGCCUCCUGAGGUUCAAGUGAUCCUCCUGCCUCAGCCUCCCAAGUAGCUGGGAUUACAGGCACAUGCCACCACACCCAGCUAAUUUUUGUAUUUUUUAGUAGAGACAGGGUUUCACCGUGUUGGCGAGACUGAUCUUGAACUCCUGACAUCAGGUGAUCCACCUGCCUCGGCCUCCCAAAGUGCUGGGAUUACAGGCAUGAGCCACCAUGCCUGGCCAGAAUAAUGUUUUUAAAUGCAGAAAAGGAAAUGCAUGGGGUUACAAGGGAAACGAAUUACACUGAAGUGUAAGCUACCAAAUAAUUUAUGAUGUGGUAGUUAUAGGUGUGCAUUUAAUAGCCAGAUCUACGAGUGGAUGUAAUAACUGCUAUGAUGUUGAAGUAGCAUAAAACAUAUAUUAGAUAUCUGCAACAACUGUGAUGUAACAUGAAAAUACCUGAUUUCUGUUGACAAAGUUACUGCUAGUACAACUGUGGAUUGUUGUCUGCACUCGUCAUUGAAGGAAAUACUAAAUUUUAGUUUUAGGCUAGUGAAAUUAAAGUUAAUUUUUCCCAUCCAAGUUCAUGUAUCUUCUGAAUUCUAUCCGUGAAUCCCUUAGAGGUCUGUGAAUUGUAGGUUAAGAACCCCUGCCCUAGCUAAUCAGAUCCACCAAUGUUUCAAAUAGGACUAUAACUUAUUCAAAGGCCAAUGAUACUUCGCAUAAUUCAAUUUUAAUAUUAUUCACAUUUCAUGUCACAAAUUUAGUAAGUUACAUGUGUUAUGUGAUGUUUUGUUUUGAUAGAUUAUAUCUUACUCCUAAAUAAAAAGUCAAGAUUUUUGUAGCAA